GCUAUUACUGCAUAUGAUGUAGGUUUAGUUUUCCAAGUUCUUCCGUGGCCCUUUUUGCUUAUUAUAUCAAUCCUUGGUGGGAGAUAGAGGAAGCAUUUUUAGUGCUAUUUUACAACUGAGGAAAUAGAGGUUUGAAGAGAACUCAGGAACUCUCAGGGUUACCCAGCAUUGUGAGUGACAGAGCCUGGAUCUGAACCAGAGCAGGCUCAUAUGAAUCAACCAACUGGGUGAAAAGAUAAGUUGCAAUCUGAGAUUUAAGACUUGAUCAGAUACCAUCUGGUGGAGGGUACCAACCAGCCUGUCUGCUCAUUUUCCUUCAGGCUGAUCCCAUAAUGCAUCCUCAAGUGGUCAUCUUAAGCCUCAUCCUACAUCUGGCAGAUUCUGUAGCUGGUUCUGUAAAGGUUGGUGGAGAGGCAGGUCCAUCUGUCACACUACCCUGCCACUACAGUGGAGCUGUCACAUCCAUGUGCUGGAAUAGAGGCUCAUGUUCUCUAUUCACAUGCCAAAAUGGCAUUGUCUGGACCAAUGGAACCCACGUCACCUAUCGGAAGGACACACGCUAUAAGCUAUUGGGGGACCUUUCAAGAAGGGAUGUCUCUUUGACCAUAGAAAAUACAGCUGUGUCUGACAGUGGCGUAUAUUGUUGCCGUGUUGAGCACCGUGGGUGGUUCAAUGACAUGAAAAUCACCGUAUCAUUGGAGAUUGUGCCACCCAAGGUCACGACUACUCCAAUUGUCACAACUGUUCCAACCGUCACGACUGUUCGAACGAGCACCACUGUUCCAACGACAACGACUGUUCCAAUGACGACUGUUCCAACGACAACUGUUCCAACAACAAUGAGCAUUCCAACGACAACGACUGUUCUGACGACAAUGACUGUUUCAACGACAACGAGCGUUCCAACGACAACGAGCAUUCCAACAACAACAAGUGUUCCAGUGACAACAACUGUCUCUACCUUUGUUCCUCCAAUGCCUUUGCCCAGGCAGAACCAUGAACCAGUAGCCACUUCACCAUCUUCACCUCAGCCAGCAGAAACCCACCCUACGACACUGCAGGGAGCAAUAAGGAGAGAACCCACCAGCUCACCAUUGUACUCUUACACAACAGAUGGGAAUGACACCGUGACAGAGUCUUCAGAUGGCCUUUGGAAUAACAAUCAAACUCAACUGUUCCUAGAACAUAGUCUACUGACGGCCAAUACCACUAAAGGAAUCUAUGCUGGAGUCUGUAUUUCUGUCUUGGUGCUUCUUGCUCUUUUGGGUGUCAUCAUUGCCAAAAAGUAUUUCUUCAAAAAGGAGGUUCAACAACUAAGUGUUUCAUUUAGCAGCCUUCAAAUUAAAGCUUUGCAAAAUGCAGUUGAAAAGGAAGUCCAAGCAGAAGACAAUAUCUACAUUGAGAAUAGUCUUUAUGCCACGGACUAAGACCCAGUGGUGCUCUUUGAGAGUUUACGCCCAUGAGUGCAGAAGACUGAACAGACAUCAGCACAUCAGACGUCUUUUAGACCCCAAGACAAUUUUUCUGUUUCAGUUUCAUCUGGCAUUCCAACAUGUCAGUGAUACUGGGUAGAGUAACUCUCUCACUCCAAACUGUGUAUAGUCAACCUCAUCAUUAAUGUAGUCCUAAUUUUUUAUGCUAAAACUGGCUCAAUCCUUCUGAUCAUUGCAGUUUUCUCUCAAAUAUGAACACUUUAUAAUUGUAUGUUCUUUUUAGACCCCAUAAAUCCUGUAUACAUCAAAGAGAA